ACAUUCCUGCUUUGCAAGGCUUUCUGCUAAGGAUGUAUUGUGGCUUUUGUUUGGAUUGCAGCAUGCAGAAUUACAGACGUUCUCCCCAGAGUUUACCUUGCUCCCCUGGUGCUAUGUGUAUGGUGAACCUGGCACUAUGGCCGCGUCUGGGACUGGCCAGACAACUGCUGCUGGCUCUCCUUAUUCCAGGAAGGAUUUAAAGGGGAAUUGCACUGCAGGCAAUGCACCAGAGCAGCAGCAUCAGGAGCUUGGGGAGUAAGGCUCCUCUGGCAUUAUUACACACAUGCAAAGCUGACCGCAAUGACAGCAGCUGCUUCUUUGAACUGUUGGCAGCAGCCAAGCGGCAGCAUGAAGUGACAGAUCACUCCUGAGCUCAAGAUGAACUCCACCUUGGAUGGUAAUCAGAGCAGCCACCCUUUUUGCCUCUUGGCAUUUGGCUAUUUGGAAACUGUCAAUUUUUGCCUUUUGGAAGUAUUGAUUAUUGUCUUUCUAACUGUAUUGAUUAUUUCUGGCAACAUCAUUGUGAUUUUUGUAUUUCACUGUGCACCUUUGUUGAACCAUCACACUACAAGUUAUUUUAUCCAGACUAUGGCAUAUGCUGACCUUUUUGUUGGGGUGAGCUGCGUGGUCCCUUCUUUAUCACUCCUCCAUCACCCCCUUCCAGUAGAGGAGUCCUUGACUUGCCAGAUAUUUGGUUUUGUAGUAUCAGUUCUGAAGAGCGUCUCCAUGGCUUCUCUGGCCUGUAUCAGCAUUGAUAGAUACAUUGCCAUUACUAAACCUUUAACCUAUAAUACUCUGGUUACACCCUGGAGACUACGCCUGUGUAUUUUCCUGAUUUGGCUAUACUCGACCCUGGUCUUCCUGCCUUCCUUUUUCCACUGGGGCAAACCUGGAUAUCAUGGAGAUGUGUUUCAGUGGUGUGCGGAGUCCUGGCACACCGACUCCUACUUCACCCUGUUCAUCGUGAUGAUGUUAUAUGCCCCAGCAGCCCUUAUUGUCUGCUUCACCUAUUUCAACAUCUUCCGCAUCUGCCAACAGCACACAAAGGAUAUCAGCGAAAGGCAAGCCCGCUUCAGCAGCCAGAGUGGGGAGACUGGGGAAGUGCAGGCCUGUCCUGAUAAGCGCUAUGCCAUGGUCCUGUUUCGAAUCACUAGUGUAUUUUACAUCCUCUGGUUGCCAUAUAUCAUCUACUUCUUGUUGGAAAGCUCCACUGGCCACAGCAACCGCUUCGCAUCCUUCUUGACCACCUGGCUUGCUAUUAGUAACAGUUUCUGCAACUGUGUAAUUUAUAGUCUCUCCAACAGUGUAUUCCAAAGAGGACUAAAGCGCCUCUCAGGGGCUAUGUGUACUUCUUGUGCAAGUCAGACUACAGCCAACGACCCUUACACAGUUAGAAGCAAAGGCCCUCUUAAUGGAUGUCAUAUCUGAAGUGGCUCAGUUACGGGGUUCCCGUGUGUGUGUGUGUGUGUGUGUGUGUGUGUGUGUGUGUGUGUGUAUUUUAUCUCUAAGUAUUCCUAAUUCACUAGGAAAUCUGGGACAGAAUACUUUGACUCUAAACAAUAGCAUACAAAUUAUUCGUAUGGAUACCUUCUAAGUUUGUAGAAAUGGUUUUCAAAAGUGCUUGUGAAUUAGAAGACUCAAGAUCAUGAAGACAAAUUGCUCUUGCUCUCAAUUUUUGAAAUGUCUUGGAAAUGACUACAGUUCUCAGAUUUAAAAUGAAUAAAGCCAUAUCUAACACCUCUUUCCAGCUGGCAUGACUGAACCUGAGUGUGAAAAGCGUCAGCAUUUUAAAAAGUCAUCACUUUCUUGUCACUUUCUGGGCUCUUUCCAGCUAUUUGGGCUUCAUAUGCAAUUGAUUUCUUCUAACGGAAUAGUAAAAUAUAAAUGAAAAGGUUUUAGAAAUUACUUUUUAUGUAUGCCAAAGCAUAACUACACUGCAAGUUUCAACACUGUCAUUUAGAAAGCCAAAUGUUCUGUGUUUUAUUCUCUUGAGAGAAUUCUCAGUAGGGUGAAUAAUGUGAACACAUAAACAUUAAUUUUAGAAUUUUACAGUGAACCAUGAAGCAAAAGUGCAAUCAAAUUAUACAAUUUAUGAAAAACUGAGCUACUUUUUGUGCCAUGCUUCACAGAGAUCUAAAGAUAUGUGUGCGUAGAAGUAAUCGUGUAGUACUUUUGCCCAUGCCUUUGUGUUAUGUCUAUAUUUAGAAUAUCUGAAUUGUUAGAUUUCUCUUUUACAGCAAAAUGUGCUUAAGCUAAAAAGUAAUUCAGUGAUAGGCUGUUGGCUGUCCAUUUUAUAAUGGUGACUAUAUACAAAAAUGUGUCUUUAAUAUUGUCUGUUCUUUCUAUUCAAAGACUUCUGAAAUAUUAGAACAUCAGGGAGAAGGGUGUCGGUCAUAAGCAACUGAGUCAGAAAGUAUACCGUAGUAUACAGAUUGUUUUUUUAAAAUACAAGGUAGUUGAGACAUUUUCUUUGUGGUUAAAUGGAAUCAACUAGUUAUUUUUGAAAAGUAUUCUUUCAGUUAGUGCUAAGGAAUCCACAUUUGAAGAGGAGAAGGGAAAACACUUAAGUCUCUUAUUGCUAUUUUCUCUCUGGAAAAAAAAUCCUUUGGCAUACAGUUCUUAAUGGUCUUUUUUUUUUUUCCUGCCAAAGUACUAGAAAAACCUAUAGGAUUUUAUAAUUCUUCUAUAGAAUUAUUAUUGAGAGUUAUGUGUGUUUGUAUGUAGUAGUGAUGUUUGUUCUUAAAAGUGAUUAUCUUUAGAGCAAGAGGUUUAUUUUUCUAAAAGGAGAGAAGGAAUUCCGGCAGCUCCAGGCACGAGAGUAUUUCCUCUACUUUUCUGCUGUUCUGGAAAUGUUCUGGAAGUCUUCAAGGGACUUACUUGAUCUCUGCCUUUGGCUAGAGGUUGUAAUCUGAAUGCGACAGUGGUGUUCAGUGAGAUGGAAGAUGGAAGAAACCCAGGGGACAUGGGUUAAAGUGGAUUUCUGAAUCCAAGAAAGGACAUGGAUAUUUAUAAAGCAGGCAGAUAAGCUUUGGUUUUCCAUCAUGAUGCCAGUGUUCUUAUGAUUUUAGGCUUUAGACAUCAACUUGAUUUUAACCUCAGUUGUGUUCUAUUUAAACUUUUUUAUUUUAAGUGACUAAGCAUUACAUAAACAUUCAAACUUCAGAUUCUGGGUUUUUCCCAAAACCUUGCUUGCUCUUUAUGUUUAGUGUUAGCAAAUUUUAUUCUAAGCUGCUUCAAAAUUUAGAACUCAUACUGAAAUUGCAAGUUAUGUUAGAAAUGGCUUGGUUAAAUUGCCAUUUCAAAUGGGAAACCUUUUCUGUUAGAUUCUGAAAAAUGGUUGUAUUGUAUACAUUUUCCCUUUAAGUGGUACAGAUCUAAAAAACCAAAAUUUACCUUUUUUCAUACAUGUUAGAGAAUGUAACCUGUUCACAUUUGCAGUUUGCUUAUGAAUUUUUAGUUUAGAAAAUAUGGCAAUUUUAAACACUUAAUUUUUGUUGAAAAAUUGAUAUUAAAUCAGCAGGUUUGAUCUUAUUUUGUUGUGUGUGUAUGUGUUGGGAGAGAGGAGAUGCUCCUGGACACAGUAGUGUCCCCUUUAGUGGCUGGGGGUGUUUUCUGUGUGAUAUAUUUGGAAAGUUCAUGUUUAACUGAACUUUUCAUCCUGGCAUAUUUAAUGCAACAUUUGAUGACAUUUAGUUUAAAUACCAGUCUGACUUCAAAAAAAAUGUAUUUUUAGAUUCAGUUACCAUGGCGUUGGCGGGAUAGCUCAUUUAACUUUAUAUGGCAUGUGACUGGUAUCAGAGGAAACAUAUACUUUUGGUGAUUAUGUUGAAAUUAUUUCAUAGUAAAUUUUAAAGUAGGAUUAUACUGAUGUUAUAUUUGUAAACUAGUUGUAUUUUUUAAUGCAGUGAUUUCAGUGAAAGUGGUUUUUUCCCCCUUCUUAGAGUAGAAAAGCAAUUACAAAUGGACUAGUGUGCUCAACUUUAGUGAGAGCAUUAUCCUGACACUAGAUUGGAUAUUUGCGUUUUUUUCACGGGCCUAUUGACUCUUACUCAAAAUUCCAUUUUGGAAAAGGUUUUCUUUAAGCUUUAUUGCUGGAUAAAUUCUUUUCAAGCCUUUUAUAAUGGCUUUUACUUUUUACUUGAAUAAUGGUCUCAGUAUUUUAAGGAUUGGGAAAACUUGAAUUUUUUUUUACCGUAAAUGCAUUGCCCACCUCCUUGAACUUGAAAAUGAAGCAGCAGGGUUAGACUCCCAGAUGGCCCAGAUGGUGGAGUGGUUUCUAGGAGGGUUUCCUCAGCUUUUCAGGUUUGUUUGAAAAAUCUGCAUGUUGACUUGGUAUAGGAAUUGUUUUAAUUUCACUGAGUAUGUUUUUGUUUCAUAGUUGUUGGUGAAAUUACCAGCAAGCCAAAAUGUAUUGUUACAUGAGCAAAUUUUGGGAAAUUUAAGAAUGGGAAAACUGUGGCAUUGAGAUUUUUUGAAGUCCUCAUAAAUCAUUUUGUGUGUUGACUUUUGUGUAAUUUUUUUCAUUUCAGGUUGAAGAAAAAAAUAUUAAGUAUUUAUAUUAAAUUUAUAUAUUAUUAAUAUUAUGUUGCAGACCUUGGAAAUAUUGUAGACAUUUCUUAUGGCUGUAAACGAGUCAUUUGGCCUUUCUUCAAAAUUUGCAUGACAAAAGGGCAUCAUAUAGUAAAAAUGAAGUUGGAACUGAGAAUAAAAAAAUGUAGGCUUCUGUUUCUAAUUAAGUAGUUUUGUAAAUGAGGGCAAGUCACUUCUCUAAAUGCUUAAUUUCUCCUAGAAGGAAAUAUUGAUCCCUUCAUACCUCAUAGGGUUAGUUUGGGGCUUGCGUUAGAUAAUAGAUGUGAAAGUACUUUGUAAAUUGUAAAGUGCUUUGCAAAUAAAAAUCAUUACUGUUAUUUGUAUCUGCCAUUCUUCUACAUGUAAGGAAGCCAUACAUCAUGAUGUGUUCCCCCACACUUUGAUCUUUGAAGCUCAAUGCUACACCACUACUCUGUGCUACUUAGCAAUCCCAGACUUGAGAAGAGAAGCAAAAUAAAUGCUCAUCCUCCUAAAAUGACAGUAGCCUUGAAUUCAACAUAAAAUUGCUUUGAUUUACUUCCUUCACUUGUCAUCAAACUCUCUGAAGGCAAGGGACAGUGUCUCUUAUCUGUCUGGUUAAUAUCUUUAUCCCCACAAUCUGACCUAGGACCUGGCUCAGAGCAGAAGUUUUAGUAAGUUUUAUAGAAUGAAUAAAUGACUCUGUAAUUAUUGCAUGUAGUCACACCAGCCUUCUCCCUUCUGUAAGGUAUUAUAGGGCAGUGAUGUUUGAAAGGUAGUCCAGAGCCUCAUAAGCAACCUUCCAUUUGGUCUAGGUUAUUCUAGAUUUUAAAUAAUAAAUAAUAUCUCUUUUUGGUAUCAAGAGAUUAAUGUGGUAAUGUGAGUCCUCUAUAUACUUAGAUAACUUUGCUUCUGGAAACUCUGUAGCUUCGGCCCAGAGAACUUCAGGCAGUGCUUUCAAAUUGCCAGUUUUUCACAGAAUGGAUUAGGAAAUAUGUAGUUGGAUCACACCUUCUUGGCUCUGGAUCCAGAUAAAGCUCUGUAAAACUGGUCACAAGGCCAAAGGAACUAUAGAAAGCCUUGAUGAAAGAAACUUCCUAUGUGGUUUUGCUUUUGUCUCCCUUUCAGCCUUUCCCAGUUUUCUAGCUCUGUCUUUCCUUCUUCCUUCCUUUUCUUACCACACUAUUGGUCAUGUAUCCAGAAAGAAGUAUUUCCUUGAUACUGCCAUAGGGUAUGGAAAAUUGUAUUAUGUAAGAGCAGUGGCUUUUAGGGAAAGUUUAAGCAAUCAAGAAGCACUUAUCUAGUAAGUUCUGCUGUGUGCCAGGUAGUAUAACUAGCCUCAGAGAGGGAUCAAAGAAGGAUCAUUCCUUUCUUGUAGAACUAUAUAGUCUUUAGGUGUUUCUUGUGGAAAAAUUCUGUGAUUAUCUGUCUUCCAGGAAGCCUCACUGUUCUCUACUUUAUCUGGAAGAAUGUACCAAGGCUUCCUGGUGGGCCACCCCCACAGCACUGUUUUUUGUGGGGUACAAUCAUAUGAUGCUGGUGUAUAAAAUCAUGUCACUUUAUUAGUUUAAGAAGUAGAUGCUGGUAAUUGAGAGCAGUCUUCUCUAUUAGCAGAUAUUUAUGGGAAGCCAAACUGUAUUCAGAAGCUUGCUUGGUGGGAAUGGAAUCUCAGAACAUGGUUCUGUAAUGUGAACAUUAUUGAGAUCAUAGUAAAAGGUGAAAUCAUCCCUGCUUCCAUUAUUGGCUAACCUACCUUCUCAUUGACAUAUUACGGUAUUUCUUUAGUUCAAUUAACUUCUGUUACUUGUCUUUUAGUCAGAUUCUUUGCAAGUCUUAGUAGUCUGCAAGCCUGCAACUCAUUCUUUCUCUUUAAGGUGCUUUUUAUAUCCCCAGCCCUAUCUUUUAUCAUAAAACAUACUAGUUUUAUGAUUUUUUUAUUAUUCAAAACACAUCUUUGUUUUUUACGUUAGUUUGAGGGAGCCGCUCAUCUUAGUUUUCAUGUAGUUCCUAGUUAGAAAAGCAAAAUACAUGAAACUACCUAUAAAAAUUAAUAGCAUCAGAUAAUUAGGGAUGUGAUAUUAAUGUCAGAUAAUGUCUAGCAAAGGAGGCAGGGAGAGGCAGAUGAGUUGGAAAGGACCUUAGGAAUCAUUUGGUCUGAUUCUGUUAUUUUGCAGAGGAGAAACCAGCCCAGUGGCCACUGGGUUAUCUAUUUAUGGUAAUACCCAGACUUCAUGCUUCCUAAUCCGUUGCUCUUUUGUAGUAUAUCAUAUUGCUUUUGCAGAGGAGUUGGAAUUUGACUUGACUCAGCCAUGCCAUGGGGUGGGCACAUGUGUAUGUGUGUAAUUCUAAGGGUAAGAAGUAUGAGCAAUAAUAUAAAUGUUAAUUGAGACUCUUUAUGUUUCAGGAGAAUUUUAUAAACUUUAUGUUAAUACUUCCAACACUGUAAGAGCUAGUGACUGUUAUUAACCCCAUUAUACAGAUGAAACAGAUUUUGAGGUGCCAGAGUCAGACAGCUUAUAAGUGGAAGAUCUGGGAUUCAAAUCUAGGACUUCUGACUCCAAAGCCUAUGUUCUUGCCUUAAUUUUUUCUUAUAUUCUACAUUUAAUUUUCACAGCAACCUAUCAGGUAGUUAUUUUGAAUUUUCCUAUUUUAUAGGUGAGGAAACAUAGGCUUAGAGAGGUUAAGAAGCUUCUAAGGUUACAUACAUAGUAAGUGUUAUGAUUCAAAUCCAAUUCUUUGACUCUAAAGCUUGUGUUCUGUACCAUUAUGUAAGCCUAGGCUUUAGAAACAUGACAGACCUCCUGCUAAAUGUAGCAGAUUGAAUAUGCAUAUUUCUGUUAACUCCACUAUAAAGAAUAGCAAAGGUAUAAUAUGGAUAAAAAGAAGGAGAACAGAGAUGAUGACAGACAGUGAUGCCAGCAGAAUUUUGGAAUAUGGAAAUUCAGUGGACGAGUAGUAACUGACUCAGCGGAAUCAACAGAGCUGCUUUCUAAAGUCAAAUGAGGAAGAGGAGCAAAAAGAAACAGCCUGAUUUGUCUAUUGACCACAGUAACUACUUGGGAAUUGGAUUGCUAAGAUGUCCCUAUAAGCAUAGAGACUAAAAAACAAGAAUUGAUAGAAGCUGAAAAACAGAGUAAUUGAUAGAAAGUUUAUAUAAGGAAUAUUUAGACAUCAUCACCCCUUACUCCUCUUCCCCAUCCCACCUGAAUCCCCAUCCCACCUGAAUCCCCAUCCCAAGCAGGCAACUGGUUUUCACCAUUGCAGCAGAAGGUGGGAGAUUUACUCUUUGGAAAAGCUGAACCACUCUAGAUGCCAGGCAUAGCUGAGAAUGGAACUAAAGGUGUGCUUUGUUGCAAACAUGACUGCUGUAAGAAAGUCUGUGUGUUAAAUAAUCAGCCCCCUUACCACACUACACUCUCAGAAUGUUCUAAGCAGGAUAUGAGAGGAGUGUAUUCUCGGGGCUGACAUUUGAGGGCUCAGAAACAAAAUAGCCACAUUCCCUGCCUGGUCACUUUAAGGUGAUGCCCAUCAAUCAACACAUCCCACCCAUGCACACAGAGCUCACAGUUUUUUAUUGCUUCACUUUUAAUAUUAACAGACAGCCAGAGAUAAUUGCACUUUUGAGAAAAAGUUCUCACAUAAAGUACAGAGCCCAAAACAAUCAAGCAAAUGACAGAAAUCAGAAGAAACAGAAAGAAUAUAGGUUGCUGAAGAAAACAACCAAAAAACCCAACUGUAACUAACAUUCUCAGAGAAGAUUUUGUAUCCAUUAAAGCAGGGGAGAACAGAGUGCAGUAAAAAUGAAUAGGAAGAGAACAAGAAAGAACUCUUGCAAUUUAAAGUAUAAUAAUUUUUUUGUUUGUUUCAGUAAGCAGGCUAGAAAAUGAAGUAGGUCAGAUAGUGAAACAAAAAGGCAGAGAGACAGAAAAUAGAUGAAAAAGCAAAACAGUCGGAGGUUUAAUCAGGGAACCCAAUAGCUGACUAACAGAAUCUUCAGAAACAGAAUAGAGGAAAAGAAAGGAAGAAAUUAAUAAAUAUCACAAGAAAAUUUUCCAGUGCUGAAAGAUACGUGUUUUCAUAAUGAAAAGGCCCAUUUCAGUGUAAUAAAAAGAUUCACAUGAUGGCAAAUUGUUAUAAAAUUUCAGAACAAUGGGGAUAAAAAUUCCUAAAAGCUUCUUGAAUGGGGUGGGGCAUGGAUGGUGGAGUCUAAACAUACAAAGUAUAGGGAUUUGAGUAGCAGAGGACUUUUUGCCACAAUAAAGCUAGAAGAUAAUGGGUAAUAGCUUCAGAAUUUUGAGGAGAAGUGAUUUCCAACCCACAAUUUUAUGCCCAAACUGUCAUUCAAGUGUGAGGGUAAACUAAACUCAUUUUGAGGUCUGCAAAAUCACAAAAUAUUCACCUGCCUUAACGUACUUUCUCGGGAAGUUACUGAAGGAUAUGCUUCUCCAGAAUGAGGGAGGAAAUAAAUAAAGAGAUACAGAAUCCAGGAAACAGGGUCUCUGACACAGGAGGAUGGUGAAAACAAUUCCCACAGGAAGGAAAGCUCUACGAAAGCAACUAUGCAGGAGACCUAGAGAGCAGCCAGUCUAAAUAGGAGCAGGAACAAAGAAGGCACUAGGAGGUAUGUCUCUAGGAAAAUAUAGUUGGGAUUUUCACCAUGGUGAGAAGAAUUUAGUUUUGUGAGAUUUUUAGGGGAAGAAUUGGUGAUAGAUACAUAGAAAACCAAGGAAAAGAAAAAGAUAGGCAAUUAAUAACUUCAGAAAAAAAUAGAAAAUUGAAGAAAGGAAAUAAGAUCAUGACAUACUCUGAUUCAGUUAUGUGUUGCUGUGUAUAGUUUGGUGUUUAGCCAAAAAUGAUAGCAACACUGUUGACAGGGUGAGGGGAAGGGAAGUGUUUGGGGGGUGAGGGGAAGGAGGGUGGGUGUAACAGAGCUACAGUAGCAUCUUCCAUAGUGUAAACUCUGAAACUGAUGUCUAAAGUGGAAAAACCCAGAAAAUAGCAACUUAAGCAUUUUAUUCAGAAGUAUGAAUUAAAAACAAACAGCUUUAAAAAAAGGAGAGGUGAAAAUGGUUGCCUCUAAGGAAUAGGGUAUGAAGAGUGAAGGGAAUUUCAUUGUAAGCUUUGUACUGUUUGACCUUUUCACUUACGUAGGUGUAUUAUUUUCUUUUUUUUUUUUUUUUUUGAGACGGAGUCUCACUCAGUCACCCAGGCUGGAGUGCAAUGGCGCGAUCUCGGCUCACUGCAAGCUCCGCCUCCCGGGUUCAGGCCAUUCUCCUGCCUCAGCCUCCCGAGUAGCUGGGACUACAGGCGCCCACCACCAUGCAUGGCUAGUUUUUUUUUGUAUUUUUAGUAGAGACGGGGUUUCACCAUGUUAUCCAGGAUGGUCUCGAUCUUCUGACCUCGUGAUCCGCCCAUCUCGGCCUCCCAAAGUGGUAGGAUUACAGGCGUGAGCCACCGCGCCCAGCCAGGUGUAUUAUUUUCUAUGAAAAGUGUAGACCACAUUUAGGAAAAGAGAUGUAUUUUAACAGAAGUAAAGGGAAAUCGGGAAGGAGGCCCAGGUAUAGAACAUUACUGAAAUAGUAAAUGGGGGCAUAAUAGCACUAUUUUACCUAUGGUUCUUUACAAAGCCAUUUCCUAUUAAUUGUCUCAUUUAAUCCCCCUAGAAGUAUAGGCAAAGUUAAUAUUGUCCCUCUUUUCCAAUUAUGGGAAUGGAGUUUUGGGUCUUUAAGACCUUUUUGGUUUCCAGUCUGCUGUAUCACUACGCCUCCAUAGGUGUCUGUUUGGAACUUUUCAGAUUUUGUAAUUUUGUUUUUUACCAAGAGAAGACAGAAGGUGCUGGAAUGCAUCCUUCUUUGACAUCGUGGGAAGGAAUAUAGGAAAACACACGUACGUGUGUGUGUGUGUGUGUGUGUGUGUGUAUGUGUAUGUAUAUGAGUAUGUGUGCUGGUACAUGAGUAUAAUACAAGACAUGGUAUUGUGAAAUGAUGAGAGGAAUGCAAAAUGCCAUGUAGUGUUCAAAGGCAAGGAGGUGCCUGUUAAAUAGAUUUCCUUAGAAGGCAGUGUGAGAGAUGGGCUAGGCUCAGGGUGGAGUAGAAUUCCUAUAGUCUGAUUCCUCUCCUCACCCCAGACCCCCUCCUUGAAUGAGAUUUCGUAAAGUAUCCAGCUGGACAGAAUUAAAGGAACCCAAAGGAUCAACAGACUAAAGACUGUAAUGAAGUGAUCUACAAUUUAACAAACAAUAUAUGACAUGAGAAAGCCCUUUGCAAAUUAAAAAACCUAUCUUUACAAGAAAUUAUUAUGAUUGUAGUUACUUAAUGAAAGAUUUGUUGGCUUGUUACAAAACGACUGAAUUAGCUUUGAGCAAAAUAUAAAAGUAAUCAUAUUUUCAAAGUAAAGUUUUAAAUUCUGUCUAUCAGCUUUCAGCAAAUACUUACUGAGUUGAAUUGUUAAGGCAAUAUUUUGGGGAGAAAGACAAAAGUUAUAGCAUUUAAAUAGCAUUAUUUAUUUUGAAAAUUUCUUCCAGAAAAACGGAGGAAACCUCAACUGCCAAAGCCAUUUAUUUUUAGCUAGACGAAAAAAUAAAGUUUAAGAAGGCCAUUUGUGGGUCUCUUGUCUUUAUUGCCUCUGGGGAACUGAAUCAGACUAAAGCCUUUUUUCAUUUAUAAAAGUUCCCCUUCUUCGUGGUAUGUAUUCGUAGGAAUCUAAGUCAUUCCUACUUAAGUUUUGUUAACAUUAUAUAUCAUUAACAUCAUUUUAUAAUACUGAGGAUGUGUAUUGUAGCCUAUAGAACACUGGAAAUAAAGUUAAAACAAAAUGUAGAUCCUAGUUCUGGCAGUUAAUUAGGUAAUCUUAAUCUGUCUGAAUGUUAGAAGGAUCUUCAUCUUUGAAUGAAGAUGACAGCAGUAUUAUAGGAGUUGGUUUAAGAUCAGUUGCAUAUUAUGUUAAUAGUAAGGCUUUUAAAGUUGUCACUGUGAUUACUUCGUACUCUUGGAUCAUUUUUUUCCUCUGAGAUAAAGAGGAAGGUAGUGAAAAGAGCAUGGAUUUUUGGAGUCUUUGGCCCUUGGUUUUCUACUCUGCAAAAUGGGAUAAUACUACCUCAUUAGAAUUAUUGUGAAAAUUAGGUACUAUCACAUCUAAAGUAUGUAAAAUUGUACUUGGGGGCAUUGUAGGAACUCAGUAAAAGAUUUCAGCUAUUAUUUCUUUGCCACACAGAGGUCAGAUUCUUCCAAUGACUUCCAGGUCCUGCAAAUUGGCACAUACCAUCAGAGGAAAGGCCUUGGGUGAAUGUGGAGUGGCCUGGUGUGCUUCCUUCUCUCAGGGAUGGUAAAUCCCUUAAGUACUGCCUUGAUAGUUAGCUCCAGUUCUUCAACUGAUGUUUUAUGUAUUUUGUCCUGCUUUUGUAAUACAUUUUGCAGUAGGGUUAGUCCUAUACAAAUCUCGGACAUUAGGAUACACAUACAAUACUUGGAUGUACUUCAUCAAGGGAAUAAUAAGUCAUUGGGGUUUACGGUAAGAAUUUUAAAUACUUCAGGAGGUGGAAAGGAAAUUUGAGGCUGAAGCGGUAAAGAGGGGUCACUUUAACCAAACUUUAAAAAUGAGUUGGUCUUAUGCAGAAAAUACAAUUUUGGCAGCUCCUAUUUUAAGCUUAAAAGGCCUGAUGAAGGGGGGCUGUUUAUAUACUUAAGGAAUAAGGAGACUGUGUAAUGUGUAGUGGCCAAAAGUAUGUGCUUGAGAGGCAGACAGACCUGGGUUUGAAUCCUAGCCCUGCCACUUACUAGCUGUGAGACCUGGGGCAAAGUACAUAAUCGUUCUAAGUCUCAGUUGUCUUAACUAAUGACACUGUCUCAUGUGAGUAUUGUAAAGAUUAAAUGAGCUAAUGCAUGUAAAGCUCUUAGCGUAGUGCUUGGCAUGCAGUAAGCACUCAGUACAUGUUAGCUGGUACAGCUGUCUUGUGAAUAGGGUAGUAUGGAUGAAGCAGAAGUUUUAAGUUGAGAUAUAAGGGAGAAUAAAUUCAGAAAGAUAAACUAGUGAUAGCUGGUCUGGAAUACAUGGCUAAGGGAUUUAAUUCUAUUUAGGAAUUGGAGGUAGACUUAAGACUUCUGAGAAAAUGAAUGACAUAAAUAUAGAAUCCUUAAGUGACAGAGCUUAGAAGAUCCCUUAGCAGACAUAAUCUGGACUCCUACUUUCACAAACAGGGAAAGAGAGACCCAGAAUAGUGACAGAGUUAAUUAUUUGCAGAACUAGGACUAGAAUCCAGGUAUUAAACCUCCUUUAGACUCAGUCAUUCCACUAGAAUAAGUCCAAAGGGUUAUUCAACAUUUGUCAAGUGCUUAGAAAAUAGGAGUUUUCAGCAGGUUUGGAAAAAAAGGAAACAACUGUUCAGAGUUUGGUUUGUGUUAAGUAAAAUCAAAGAAUUGUCUUUCCAUUGGUACUUUCAGCCAAACGAGUUAAGAUUUUCUUUCAGUACUAAUCAAAAUGUUCUCUUGAUCACUAGUAACAACCUCAGAAAUGUUUGUUCGAGGAGGUAAAAAAUAAAUGGGUAUUUCUAGAAUUCUUUCAUUGGUAUUUAUAAUUGUACUGCUAGUGAGUUUGAAGGGUAAAGUUUUUGCUUAAAUAAAAUGGAAGAUCAUAAGUUGUCUAGUAACUUUUAAAGUAGCUGUUUUCCAAGAAUUUUAAAUAUGAAAAUAUAAAAAGUUUAAUUCUAGGAGAGUCCUUUAAGGCAUUACUACAUAGAUACUAAUAUACUUUGCUUGGGAUUAUUUCCUAUGUGCUGAUAAGUUUUAAGUUUUUUAGUUAAUAGAAAAAGAUCUGGUUUACUUAUAGCUUUAUACUUCUAAAAUAAGAUAGCUUUUAAGUAUUGUUUUUUGAUACUUAUUAAGAUUCUUCCAUAGAAAAAUUAAAAUCUUCAAUAUGAUUUUUCUUAUAUGUUGAGCUCAAGAAAAUAUUUUUGCCUAAAAGCUUUAUAAAAAUUCAAAAUUAAAAUAAAGGUUGAAACCUCAGAAUAUAUACCUGUAGCCUUUGAAUAUGGGUGUGAAUGCAGACCUCUUACGGAAUUCUUAAUGCAGUGCAGCAGUUCACUGAUGGAGCUGUUACAUGACUGGUAUCAUUCAAACACAGAUUUUCAUUUAAUAUUUGUUAAUUGUUAUAAGAGCAAAAAUAUCUAGCCAUUUUACAGCUGCUGGGUUUUUUUUUUUUUUUUUUUUUUUUUUUUUUUUUUUUGAGACGGAGUCUUGCUCUUGCUGCCCAGGCUGGAGUGCAAUGGCGCGAUCUCGGCCCACUGCGAACCUCCGCCUCCCAGGUUCAAGCGAUUCUCCUGCCUUAGCCUCCUGAGAAGCCGGGAUUACAGGUGUGCAUCACCACGCCCAGCUAAUUUUGUAUUUUUAGUAGAGAUGGGGUUUCACCAUGUUGGCCAGGCUGGUCUCGAACUCCUGACCUCAGGUGAUCCGUCCAUCUUGGCCUCCCAAAGUGUUAGGAUUACAGGCGUGAGCCAUCAUGCCCAAUCAACUGCUGUAUAUUUUUGCUACUCAAUAGACACAUUUAAAUCUCUGAUUUGUGACUUAUUUCAGAAGAGAAGCUAACUUUGUAAAGUAAAACUGAGUAUUUGUUAGCAUUUUGAAGCAUUUAUAAGCAUUUUCUUGGAAAUAAUCCAUUGAUUCGAUUAUUUAAAAAUAUAACUUGAGCAAUAUGAGACUUGGUCCUCUGUGUGUCUGUGUGUUGCAUGUUAUUAGUAGGUGAUUUUGAGAAGAUUUUAUCCAUAGCAUACAACGCUUUACAAAAUCUUUAAACAAAUAGUACAAGUCAAACAAUACAGUACGUAUUAAGCUGUACUAAGAGAGCAUUUGAUAUGCAGUUUACUUGGUAAUAAUACAAUGAAAUAAGUAUUUGGAAGUUCAUCACAGUUAUCAGAAACAUUUGUUUGGAAUAUGACUUUGCAUAUAAUAAUUUUAUGUCUUAGUUCACCCAUAAAUUACCUUCCCCCUUUGACUAUCACCACCUCUUAAAUCAAAAUGAUAUUUUGUGUGUUCACUUUUGUCAGGUAACAGUACUUGAGUAUUUCCUGCUUCUUGGGCCUCUCCAUGAUGGAUUGCUGUGAAGGAGAAUCAACAAUAGCAAACCAGGAAAAGGUUGACAGUGCAGUUAGCAUUUAUGUCUUAUUUAUACAUGAUUUGGGACCGUUUUGCCAAACAUUGAAUAAUUUUCCUGUGGGAAACUUGAGCCCUAAAAGGAAAUGAACAUAGCUAAAAGGCUGCAUAUCACAUGGGACUUAGAUUUAUUUUUAGAAUGGCACUAUAAUGCCAUAUUUGGAUUGAAACAAUGUGAUAGCAGUAAAAUAUUUCAUUAAAUAAAGAGCCAUCUUUUCUGAGGAA